ACGGUCACUGACAGCGUGAGCCCGCGGCGGCUGCUGCCAUGGUGGCUGGCGGCCGGGUAAGGGUCUGAGUGGAUCUCCUGCCAGGCCAGAGCGCCUUCGGGGGCCGCGGCGGAAGGCCAGGAGUUUGCAGCCAGGGCGCCGGGUUUGUGGUCUGCAGUGUCGUGAGGCUGAGGUGCAGCAUGUCUAGACUGGGAGCCCUGGGUGGUGCCCGUGCCGGGCUGGGACUGUUGCUGGGUACCGCCGCCGGCCUUGGAUUCCUGUGCCUCCUUUACAGCCAGCGAUGGAAACGGACCCAGCGUCAUGGCCGCAGCCAGAGCCUGCCCAACUCCCUGGACUAUACGCAGACUUCAGAUCCCGGACGCCACGUGAUGCUCCUGCGGGCUGUCCCAGGUGGGGCUGGAGAUGCCUCAGUGCUGCCCAGCCUUCCACGGGAAGGACAGGAGAAGGUGCUGGACCGCCUGGACUUUGUGCUGACCAGCCUUGUGGCGCUGCGGCGGGAGGUGGAGGAGCUGAGAAGCAGCCUGCGAGGGCUUGCGGGGGAGAUUGUUGGGGAGGUCCGCCCUUUAAUGAGGAGCAGUAGUAAGAGGCACCCCAUGGUGAGCAGAAAGACAAGCUGGAUGGGACCUAAUGGUACCCUUCGGGAUGGGGCCUGCUUUCCAGAUGCCACAUGGAAGAGAACCAGAGAGUGGCUCGGCGGCGAAGGUUUCCGUUUGUCCGGGAGAGGAGUGACUCCACUGGCUCCAGCUCUGUCUACUUCACGGCCUCCUCGGGAGCCACGUUCACAGAUGCUGAGAGUGAAGGGGGUUACACAACAGCCAAUGCGGAGUCUGACAAUGAGCGGGACUCUGACAAAGAAAGUGAGGACGGGGAAGAUGAAGUGAGCUGUGAGACUGUGAAGAUGGGGAGAAAGGAUUCUCUUGACUUGGAGGAAGAGGCAGCUUCAGGUGCCUCCAGUGCCCUGGAGGCUGGAGGUUCCUCAGGCUUGGAGGAUGUGCUGCCCCUCCUGCAGCAGGCCGACGAGCUGCACAGGGGUGAUGAGCAAGGCAAGCGGGAGGGCUUCCAGCUGCUGCUCAACAACAAGCUGGUGUAUGGAAGCCGGCAGGACUUUCUCUGGCGCCUGGCCCGAGCCUACAGUGACAUGUGUGAGCUCACUGAGGAGGUGAGCGAGAAGAAGUCAUAUGCCCUAGAUGGAAAAGAAGAAGCAGAGGCUGCUCUGGAGAAGGGGGAUGAGAGUGCUGACUGUCACCUGUGGUAUGCGGUGCUUUGUGGUCAGCUGGCUGAGCAUGAGAGCAUCCAGAGGCGCAUCCAGAGUGGCUUUAGCUUCAAGGAGCAUGUGGACAAAGCCAUUGCUCUCCAGCCAGAAAACCCCAUGGCUCACUUUCUUCUUGGCAGGUGGUGCUAUCAGGUCUCUCACCUGAGCUGGCUAGAAAAAAAAACUGCUACAGCCUUGCUUGAAAGCCCUCUCAGUGCCACUGUGGAAGAUGCCCUCCAGAGCUUCCUAAAGGCUGAAGAACUACAGCCAGGAUUUUCCAAAGCAGGAAGGGUAUAUAUUUCCAAGUGCUACAGAGAACUAGGGAAAAACUCUGAAGCUAGAUGGUGGAUGAAGUUGGCCCUGGAGCUGCCAGAUGUCACGAAGGAGGAUUUGGCUAUCCAGAAGGACCUGGAAGAACUGGAAGUCAUUUUACGAGACUAACCACGUUUCACUGGCCUUCAUGACUUGAUGCCACUAUUUAAGGUGGGGGGGCGGGGAGGCUUUUUUCCUUAGACCUUGCUGAGAUCAGGAAACCACACAAAUCUGUCUCCUGGGUCUGACUGCUACCCACUACCACUCCCCAUUAGUUAAUUUAUUCUAACCUCUAACCUAAUCUAGAAUUGGGGCAGUACUCAUGGCUUCCGUUUCUGUUGUUCUCUCCCUUGAGUAAUCUCUUAAAAAAAUCAAGAUUCACACCUGCCCCAGGAUUACACAUGGGUAGAGCCUGCAAGACCUGAGACCUUCCAAUUGCUGGUGAGGUGGAUGAACUUCAAAGCUAUAGGAACAAAGCACAUAACUUGUCACUUUAAUCUUUUUCACUGACUAAUAGGACUCAGUACAUAUAGUCUUAAGAUCAUACCUUACCUACCAAGGUAAAAAGAGGGAUCAGAGUGGCCCACAGACAUUGCUUUCUUAUCACCUAUCAUGUGAAUUCUACCUGUAUUCCUGGGCUGGACCACUUGAUAACUUCCAGUGUCCUGGCAGCUUUUGGAAUGACAGCAGUGGUAUGGGGUUUAUGAUGCUAUAAAACAAUGUCUGAAAAGUUGCCUAGAAUAUAUUUUGUUACAAACUUGAAAUAAACCAAAUUUGAUGUUA